GAAUGUCCCGGGUGGAGCUGGCUGAGUCGCGCGCUCUGCUCCACCCGACGGGGCUGUGUGUGCUGGGCCUGGCUCGCGGCGAACCGAGAUGGCAGAGCAGUCGGACGAGGCCGUGAAGUACUACACCCUAGAGGAGAUUCAGAAGCACAACCACAGCAAGAGCACCUGGCUGAUCCUGCACCACAAGGUGUACGAUUUGACCAAAUUUCUGGAAGAGCAUCCUGGUGGGGAAGAAGUUUUAAGGGAACAAGCUGGAGGUGACGCUACUGAGAACUUUGAGGAUGUCGGGCACUCUACAGAUGCCAGGGAAAUGUCCAAAACAUUCAUCAUUGGGGAGCUCCAUCCAGAUGACAGACCAAAGUUAAACAAGCCUCCGGAACCUUAAAGGCGGUGUUUCAAGGAAACUCUUAUCACUACUAUUGAUUCUAGUUCCAGUUGGUGGACCAACUGGGUGAUCCCUGCCAUCUCUGCAGUGGCCGUCGCCUUGAUGUAUCGCCUAUACAUGGCAGAGGACUGAACACCUCCUCAGAAGUCAGCGCAGGAAGAGCCUGCUUUGGACACGGGAGAAAAGAAGCCAUUGCUAACUACUUCAACUGACAGAAACCUUCACUUGAAAACAAUGAUUUUAAUAUAUCUCUUUCUUUUUCUUCCGACAUUAGAAACAAAACAAAAAGAACUGUCCUUUCUGCGCUCAAAUUUUUCGAGUGUGCCUUUUUAUUCAUCUACUUUAUUUUGAUGUUUCCUUAAUGUGUAAUUUACUUAUUAUAAGCAUGAUCUUUUAAAAAUAUAUUUGGCUUUUAAAGUAUGCACCGUGUUUGCCUGUUUGGUGUAUAAUUGUCUUUAAUGUUUAGAAUCUGGUUAUUUAGAGGAUUCCUUCAAUGUGUUACUCAUCCAGACCCACAGAGGCCAUAUGACUGGAGGUGCGGGAAAUAGGUUUGAGUGUCUCCUUUCACAUCGUCACAUCUCAUUGAGUAACCAUGUAUUGUAUGCUUCCGAUAUAGUUUCUUUUUUUCAAGGAAAUUAAGAAAGGCCAGAAAUUAUAGUUUAAGGAUUUCUAAUAAUUGUCCUACUUGAAAUAGAUCUUAAAAAGAAAGUAGCGGCUGGGCAUCGUGGCUCACACCUGUAAGCCCAGCACUUUGGGAGGCUGAGGUGGGUGGAUCACUUGAGGUCAGGAGUUCAAGACCAGCCUGACCAACAUGGUGAAACCCUGUCUCUACUAAAAAUACAAAAUUAGCAGGGCGUAGUGGCGCAUGCCUGUAAUCCCGGCUACUUGGGAGGCUGAGGCAGGAGAAUUGCUUGAACCCAGGAGGCAGAGGUUGUAGUGAGCUGAGAUCGCGCCGUUGAACUCCAGCUGGGCAACAAGAGUGAAACUCUGUCUCAAAAAAAAAAGAAAGUAGCCUACAGGGCCUAUAAGAGAGACUUCUUAUCUUCACUGAUUGAAAAACAUCAGCAACUUAAAAACACAUGAACCAUGAGAGGGCAUCGCAACUGUCCAUUCUCUCAGCUUACACGUAUCAUUGCAAAGGCACUCACAGCUUCAUAGGUUCUAAAGUUUUAAGAAUUCCUCAUUCAGAGAGUAGAAUUGUUUGUAAACUCUUCUAAGGAAAGGCUGGUUUUCUAAUUUGUAAGGAGAUUGUGGGACAUUGGAAUCUGAUCUUUGAAGAAAUUUAGCGGCUAGUGUCAAGCUCUGAAGAGUUCUGGUGUGGCUCUGUCUCCUCCUGGGGGCUCUAAGGGGCUGAUUCAGUCAUCUUACUUCCCAUUUAUUAUUCUCUGCCUUAUGUGUUAUUCUUUUAAAUGUGGAAACUUGAAAGCUGAAUUUGUUAGAACCCAGUACAUGUGUCAUUGGCUGUGACUGCAUUUGCACUGGCAUGAGCUGACAAACCACGAGGUUCUUCAGAAGUGACCGCGUGCAGUGGAAAGGAAUUGUGUUGUUCUUACAGAGUACAACCUUUAUAAUCAAAUAGGAUGCACCGCCUUUGCCUUCUUUAGUCACUGAAAGUUGACAAGUAGUUUCUAUUUCAAAAUAAAUUACAACACUUGUUAAGGGACCUAUGUAAAUAUUUCAAUAUUUUUGGUUGUGAUUUUUAGCUAUAAAGCUUCACAUUUUAGUAGUUUUUAAAACAUUGCUCCUAAAUCAACUAUGAAGUGAAUCGAAGUGGGUCAGUCGUACCUUAGAUGACAUUAAAGGGUUAACUUGUAAAUCAUUUUUAAGAUGUUGAGUAAUAGCAUCUGUAUAUCGUUAAGAAACAUAACAGUUGAACUUUGACAUUUUUAUCAGUGACUCAGCAAUUUGCUGCUGUGGCUGGCAAUGUUUCUUCAUGUGUUUUGGGAACAACAUGUGGAGUAAAGGAGAGUUUACUUCCUAAUUUUAACAUUUACAGUUUGUGCAGCCAGACUCUCAAGGAAAGAUAUUUGACACUUUUUUCUCUAUUGCUUUCCCUUCAGAGAGGUGAGAGACUUCAGAGGCUGCCCUUUCUUUUCAUCUGCUGCUUGUGAAAGGAAAACAUCUUGGGCCCCCAGAAUCACUAAGGAAAACUCAAGCUGGAAACUGCUUAGGGCCAACCUGCCUCCCAUUCUACUCAGUCAAGCCUCUGCUCACUGAGAGAGAGGCAUAUCUGAUUGCUUCCUUUGGAAAGGCUAAUCAGAAACUCAGAAGAAUGCAACCCUUUGUGUCUCACCUCUCUGUGACCUGGAAGCUCCCUCCUGCUUUGAGUCUUCCUGCCUUUGCUUCAAGGUGUCCCGCCUUUCCAAACAGAACCAAUGUACUUCUUACAUAUAUUGAUCAAUGUCUCAUGUCUCCCUAAAAUGCAUAAAACCAAGCUGUGCCCUGACCACCUUGGGUACAUGUCAUUAGGACCUCCUGAUGCUUUGUCACGGGCAUGUCCUCAACCUUGGCAAAGUAAACUUUCUUUUUUUUUUUUUUUUGUUUUUGAGACAGAGUCUCACUCUGUCGCCCAGGCUGGAGUGCAGUGGUAUGAUCUUGGCUCACUGCAACCUCCGACUCCCAGGUUCAAGUGAUUCUCCUGCCCCAGCCUCCUGAGUAGCUGGGACUACAGGCGUAUGCCACCAUGCCUAGCUAAUUUUUUUGUAUUUUUAGUAGAGACGGGAUUUCACCAUGUUAGCCAGGCUGGUCUUGAACUCCUGACCUCAGGCAAUCCACCCGCCUCAGGCUCGCAAAGUGCUGGAAUUACAGGCAUGAGCCACUGUGCCGGGCCUAUUCCUUGACUUUCUUAAUAAAGUUGUUUUCACUUUGCA